CUCUAGGCGCCGGCCCCGGAGCCCGGUCCGCGAGCAGCGGCGGCUGCCGGAGGGACGAUGAGCUGCGCGGGGCGGGCGGGCCCUGCCCGGCUCGCCGCGCUCGCCCUGCUGACCUGCAGCCUGUGGCCGGCACGGGCAGACAACGCGAGCCAGGAGUACUACACGGCGCUCAUCAACGUGACGGUGCAGGAGCCCGGCCGCGGCGCCCCGCUCACGUUUCGCAUCGACCGCGGGCGCUACGGGCUUGACUCCCCCAAGGCCGAGGUCCGCGGCCAGGUGCUGGCGCCGCUGCCCCUCCACGGAGUUGCUGAUCAUCUGGGCUGUGAUCCACAAACCCGGUUCUUUGUCCCUCCUAAUAUCAAACAGUGGAUUGCCUUGCUGCAGAGGGGAAACUGCACGUUUAAAGAGAAAAUAUCACGGGCCGCUUUCCACAAUGCAGUUGCUGUAGUCAUCUACAAUAAUAAAUCCAAAGAGGAGCCAGUUACCAUGACUCAUCCAGGCACUGGAGAUAUUAUUGCUGUCAUGAUAACAGAAUUGAGGGGUAAGGAUAUUUUGAGUUAUCUGGAGAAAAACAUCUCUGUACAAAUGACAAUAGCUGUUGGAACUCGAAUGCCACCGAAGAACUUCAGCCGUGGCUCUCUAGUCUUCGUGUCAAUAUCCUUUAUUGUUUUGAUGAUUAUUUCUUCAGCAUGGCUCAUAUUCUACUUCAUUCAGAAGAUCAGGUACACAAAUGCACGCGACAGGAACCAGCGUCGUCUCGGAGAUGCAGCCAAGAAAGCCAUCAGUAAAUUGACAACCAGGACAGUAAAGAAGGGUGACAAGGAAACUGACCCAGACUUUGAUCAUUGUGCAGUCUGCAUAGAGAGCUAUAAGCAGAAUGAUGUCGUCCGAAUUCUCCCCUGCAAGCAUGUUUUCCACAAAUCCUGCGUGGAUCCCUGGCUUAGUGAACAUUGUACCUGUCCUAUGUGCAAACUUAAUAUAUUGAAGGCCCUGGGAAUUGUGCCGAAUUUGCCAUGUACUGAUAACGUAGCAUUCGAUAUGGAAAGGCUCACCAGAACCCAAGCUGUUAACCGAAGAUCAGCCCUCGGCGACCUCGCCGGCGACAACUCCCUUGGCCUUGAGCCACUUCGAACUUCGGGGAUCUCACCUCUUCCUCAGGAUGGGGAGCUCACUCCGAGAACAGGAGAAAUCAACAUUGCAGUAACAAGUGGUCACUUCUUUCAUCGAAACUCCUUGUCCCCUCGGAGUCUGGUGUAUGAAAGUGAAUUCUCCACCAUCGAACCUUCUUUGGACAUGUAUGAUGAGAACAAAACCUGAAUUUUAAACAUGGCCUGGCUGUUGGGGUCACUGCUUUUGUGAUUUGAUUUCUGAUCACCUUUCUUAUUUUGUAUUCUCCUGUCAGCAUCCGUUUUGGAAGAAUGGCAGCACUUUCCAAGCACAGGUUGGGGUUCAGGGUUAAUUUGCAAAGUUCCCCCAAGGUGAGGCUUUGAGGACAGUAGCAUUGCCCAGGUGAGCCUUGUGGUAUUGAAAACCCGCCCAAGCUGAUCAUUGAAGGUGGGCGCCCAGCAAGGCUGGCUGUUUCCAGAGAAGAGGCCGGGCCCAGGAUUAAUGUUGCAUUGCAGACGCAUCUCUGAACAAUCACAUGCUGUUCUGCACCAGGGAAGCUGGGGUUUUUAACAUCCUUUUGUGGUCCCUGCUUACGAUGCAUACUGCCCUGUGGGAGAAGCUUCCUACCCGCGUGGAGUACAGGUGCUGCUCCCUGACCUGGCUCUGGAUGUUCCCCUCUCGCUUAUUCUACUUCCUGCUGAAGGGCCCCUUCUAAAGGGGGUUGAGAGAAGGCCUUGCCUUUGUAUCUCCUCUGAGACUCUGACCACCCACUUCCUGCCAGGGCAGGGCCGUGGGAGACCCAGGCCGUGGGGCCGGGUCUGUGUGCGGGGCCAGGCAGCCGUCUGCGUCGCUGUUUUCCAGCCUCCGUGUUGAGCAUGACGUAAAGUGACAAGUGUUUAAGUCAGCACGAAAACACUGAAGGCCCCUCCGUCCCUGCAGCCUGUGAACACGUCUACUCGGCCACCCGUCAGUAUAGGGAGUGUGUGUAUAGGGAGGUGGCACCUGGGAGCCCAGCCCAGCAGUGUCUCUGGGCACAGUGAUUUCAGGGGGAUGGCCAGCAGUUGUGAAAGACAGAAUGAUCUGGAAUGUCUCAUUGGGAAGACCAAACCCCCUUCUCGCUGCAGAUACCAGAUAAGCACCCAUCUUCACUGUCCACUGUGCAGCCCAGUCCCCUCCAGCAGCCCCAGCACAGCAUGAAGAAGGCACAUGAGCACCGGCCGACAGGCUUACAGGACAGGGUGCAGUGGCCAGCAUCCCAGGCAUCAGGGACAUGUGGGAUCUUCCCACACACCUGGGAUGACAUCGAAUUAACAUGAUGAGAAAAUUGCAUCUUACUGCUAAUCCCAGUACAGAACCACUAUGGGCAAAUUUAUAAAACUAAUCUGCACACCCUCUUUGCAAAAGGACACACCUGAGUUGAGUCUGCCUCUCAUUGGCAUGAGCUUUGUGGGGGCGUGAGGCGCACAGACCCUUGCUGUGAGAACAGGAACCCCAGUCUCCACAUGCCCAGGGUCAGAUCCGACAGCAAACGAAGCAGAUGCGUGAAUCCCCUGCCCUGUUCUCACUGACUGUGGAAUAUACGUUUGAAGUGAACACUUGCCAUUUUUCCACGUGCAGCUUCUCCUAAAGUGUCUUUUCUCCUAACGCGUCAAUAACGCCUCAGACACAGGUGUGCCUGAAGGAAACCUGCAGAGCCCCGGAUGGGGACAGGCUUCAGGAGCAUUGUCAGAGAGCGGGCAGCGGCAUUUCGUUUUCGCUCAUUUGAGGCUAGAAUGGUGCAGAUUUUAAAGGUCUUAGCAGCUUUUGUGUUUUACCUUUUACCAAGGGCUUUGGGGGUUUUUUUGUUUUGUUUUUCUUUAUGAUAGUCUUCGUACUAUAAAAAUAUUUUCAAUGAGCAGCUUCAAUAUAGCAUCGUUCAGAAAAGCAGGUUUCCCCAUUGGGCUCUCAGAGAGAGGGUGAGUCUGCAGGAAGCUGGAGCCCAUUUGCUGGAGGUUCCAGACACGCGUCUGCAUUUGUAUGUGUUUGACCCACCUGAAAGGUAGGAGAGCUCAGUUCGGAUCAUUGCCGUGUUGUCUAUACCACCUCCUUGUUUUCCCAAACCAAAACGCAGAUCCUGAUGUAGCAUUUUCUCCUGAUUUGAGGUCUUACCAAUGUGUAUACGUUAAAUUCCACUCAAGACAGUUUCUUUACUGAAAAGGUAUGAAAUUACGUGAGAAGAAGUACAAAUUUCAGGCCCCUAGAAUCUGUCUAUUAAUAUAACAUUUGAAUUUCUGGGAAAUCUGGGGCACACAUUCACGGUAGAAUAACAAGGAGGCAUUGCUUGCAGGGGAGCGUACUCAGAACAGUGCUGUGGAUCCUGGCUUGACACCCUUUUCUGGAAAAUUGGGGUCACUCUCUGGCUCAGCUACAGAAUGGCCUGUCUUUGUCAGGAGGGACACUAACUUCUCAUUAAGGCCAUGCUCUUCAGGAACAGAGAGGAUGAUUUGGUUUUUGGUUUCAGGUUUUUAUUUUUAUUUUUGUUUUGAGACAGUCUCACUCUGUCACCCAGGCUGAAGGGCAGUGGCGCAACCUUGGCUCACUGCAGCCUCCACCUCCUGGGCUCAAGUGAUCCUCCCACCUCAGCCCACCGAGUAGCUGGCACCACAGGCACGUGCCACCACACCCAGCUAAUUUUUGGAUUUUCUGUAGAGAUAUGGGACUUUGCCAUGUUGCCCAGGCUGGUCUUGAAUUCCUGGGCUCAAGCAAUCCACCCCCACCUCGGCCUCCCAAAGUUCCGGGAUUCCAGUUGUGAGCCACCAUGCCCAGCCAAGAAUGGCAUUUUUUUUUUAAUCCCAAAUAACAGCCUCUUUACUAGCUGCUAUGCUGGGGGAAAUCCCUGCUAAGUCGGGACCCUGGCAGGAAGUGGCCGGGGCUGCUUGUCCGGUGAGCAUUGUGAAGACACACGUCGCCACAUGGGCAGCGCUUCCCUGAGGCGCUUGGGGAGCAGUGUUCCGCCUGCUGCAGGUGUGAUGGGGUGCAGAGAGUGAGUGCCUCCGUGGUUGCAAGUCUUGCCACCAGCAGCGGUUAUUAGGAAAUGUAUGAUAACCUCAGUCAUUGUUGAGGGGGGAACUGUUUGAAGUAAGGAAGAGGCUGAGGAGUCAGCUAUUUACACCACACAUCCACCCCCCUGCCUCCAGUGGACUGCUGUGAGCUGGGCCUGUGCCCGGGUGAGGAGACCAUGGGCCUGUGUGGCAGGAUCAGCAAGUCUAGGGCCAGGGCAGCCAUCAGCAUCCUCUGGGAGUUGGUUGUGACUAUUGAAAUGCAAAUGCUUCCGCUUUGGUGAUUUUUUUUUUUUUUGAGACGGAGUCUUGCUCUGUCACCCAGGCUGGAGUGCAGUGGCGCGAUCUUGGCUCACUGCAACUUCCGCCUCCCGGGUUCACACCAUCCUCCUGCCUCAGCCUCCCGAGCAGCUGGGACUACAGGCACCUGCCACGACGCCCAGCUAAUUUUUUGUAUUUUUAGUAGAGAUGGGGUUUUACUGUGUUAGCCAGGCUGGUCUCGAUCUCCUGACCUCGUGAUCCGCCUGCCUUGGCCUCCCAAAGUGCUGGGAUUACAGGCAUGAGCCACCACGCCUGGCCAAGCUUUGGUGACUUUUAACAUCCUAAGGGAGGAGUAACCCCUCUUUCCUGUUAAUCCAGAGGGAGGGGAGGGAAGGCCAGAUAGCCAGGGCUUCCAGCGCAGGAGGCAGAGCUUGGCAGCCACUGAUGGUGGUAAGCAUGUCUGCCCAGGGCUGCCUGCCUCUGCCCUCCUCUUGGGAAGACAAGCUCUGCCCCCAGCUAAAAACUCCUCACAACCCUGAUGAGCCUUGCUUUUGCAGAGAGGCCCCAGCUCCCCUGGUGGUCCUCAGGCCUGGCUGCGAGGCACAUUCACGAGGCACUGCCUUGAGCACUGAGGUCUGGCACCUGCCGGCUUCCCUGAUGCGGCAACAGCCCCAGCUGCCAGUGAGUCUGAUGAUAUUUGGAAAAGUAUUUUUAAAAACGAGAUUACUGAAUUUUACAAGCUUGACAUUUUCUAUUGGCUUUAUAAGCUCUUCUCAUGUUUUUAUUACCCUCACAUCCAAUCCGUUCGAGCUACACGCUAAAUCAAAUUGGUAUUUUAUAUUUUUAUUUUUUUAGAGGCAGGAUCUCGCUCUGUCACCCAGGCAGGAGUGCAGUGGCACAGUCAUGGCUCGCUGCAGCCUUGACCUCGCCUCAGCCUCCCCAGUAGCUGGGACCACAGGCUCAUGCCACGCACGCCCGGCUGAAGCUAGUUUUAACUGAAGAAAACUCAAAGUGUUCUCUCGCCGUUAACCUUUAUUAUUGAGGCAUUGGCUCUGCUAUAGGAAAACGAGGUGACGUUAAUGUCGGUGGUUGACAUUAACCACUGGCAAGUGACAGUGUGGCUCCUUGACAAGUGGUUGCUGCUCAUAAAUGUCAUGAAACAAAAACACUGAUUUUAGAGAAGUGGGAUUCUACAGUUAAUAUCGCCAGCAAACUUUUAUUAAGCUCUCACUCUGUGCCAAACACAUGCUUGAAGUUGGGGUGAAUCUGUGACCAUUAAGAUGUUGGCUGUUCAUGGGCACGUUAUCAAGCAACUGGGGUGUGAGAGCGAAUGAUAAGAGGGUGAAUCUGGAUGAGGAGGGACUUCCAGGGCACAGGUGGAGGAGAGGCAUUGCAGCCAUAGAGAGGCCCAAGGGAACAGUCAAGACAAGGCGGGGACAGUGGCCAGGAGGCGAGGGCAGCACUUCCUGGGCAGGGAAGGCUUGCCAGGGAGACCAGACUCCUGUCUCUGUUUGGAAAGAAAAGGAACCGCACUGGGGGUCAGGGAGGCUAGGCACGGCACCAGCCUGGGAUGCCAGUCCCGCCUGAGGGGCCAAGGCAAAGGGGAAGCAUUCACAGACCCCACACCAGGCUCUGACGCCAAGUGGAAGAAGAGGGAGAUAGAAGCAGAAGCCUGGGCUUCCAGGCCUGGUUCCUGGGCGGGUGUUGAUGGGACCCAGGGAGAGUCCUGUGGGGAUACUUUGGGUCUGGGCUGGCAGGGGCUCUGGAAGGAGAGGCAUGGAGGUGCGAACCUGGUGCCCAGGUGGAGGUGCAGUGGGGGUAAGGUGGCCAGGCUGCAGACCCCUGCAUCAGAAUGCCUGCGAAGCUGUGGGUUUUUUGUUUGUUUGUUUGUUUUAUUUCGAGACAGGGUGUCACUCUGUCGCCCAGACUGGAGUGCAGUAGCGCCGUCUCGGCUCACUGCAAGCUCCGCCUCCCAGGAUCAAGUGAUUCUCCUGCCUCAGCCUCCCGAGUAGCUGGAUUUACAGAUGCAUGCCACCACGCCCAGCUAAUUUUUUGUAUUUUUAGUAGAAACGAGGUUUCACCACGUUGGCCAGGCUGGUCUCAAACUCCUGACCUCAAAUGAUCCACCUGCCUCGUCCUCCCAAGUGCUGGAAUUACAGGUGUGAGCCGCACCAGCCUGUUUUUUAAUUUUAUUUAGAGACAGGGUCUCACUCUGUUGCCCAGACUGGAGUGCAGUGGUGUAAUCUUGGCUCACUGCAGCCUCAACUUCCAGCGCUAAAGCAAUCCUCCCACCUCUGCCUCCCGAGUAACUGGGACUACACACGCAUGCCACUACACCCAGGUAAUUUUUAAAAAUUUUUUUUAGAGACAGAGCUUCUCCAUGUUGCCCAGGCUAGCCUCAAACUCCUGGGCUCCAGUGACCCUCCCGCCUUAGUGUCUCAAAGUGCUGGGAUUACAGGUAUGAGCCACCACGCCCGGUCAGAAGCUGUGUUUUUAAGUGGACAUACCAUCUUGUCCUGCUGAAGUAUCUCCAUGUAAUCACAAUAUCUAUGUCACCCAAAUCUCCUCCUUCCUCCUCCCUCCCCCAAAACACCCCCACAGGCAUGCAUACCCUCCCAUGCGCUGGAGGCAGAAUCUCCCAAGGGGAGCUGGCCAGGAGAGGUGUCCCUGAGUUCAGAUGGAGGUGGAAGCCAGAGUGGGGCUGGGACCACCCAGUGACAUGAGGAUGGGGCUUGGGAUAAAGCCCUGGGGACACUGACAUUUAAAGUGUGGACAGAAGGAGCUACUGAAGGCAAUGGAUUUAGAAAAGCAAUUGAGUAUGAUUUCCUUCUUCAAGAAAGGCUGUCCAACUAGCUCUCACUUCCUCUCGUGUGUUCAGUGUCACCCGGAAGCAGAGUUUAAUGUGACUAAAGUCAACAUUGGCUCACACUGUCAGGGAGUGUGGGAAGAUGAGUAAGGACUCAUCGCAGGGCGAUACCCACAGCUUAAAAUAGGCACCUUCCCCUCCCAGGUCUGGUUAGGGCAGUUGUUACAUAUGAGGGGCGUGGAGUUUUGUCUUGUAUUUUGGCCUUGUUGGUAAAGCAUUCCAAAGCUUCGACACACCCUCCUUUCAGCCCAUUAGGAAAGGCUGUUGAUUGUAAUAUUCACACAGCUCCCUGGGCUAUGGUUAAGAGCCUUGCAGAAGGACUGGGAGAAGCCCUGUGUGUUUGAAGUAUUGUAGCAUCAGAAAAAAACACCGGAAGAAGGCAGGUGGGGACAAGGUGCCUAUGUCUGCUCCUUGGAAUUCCUUUCCUUACUGUCCGAGGCAACUACAGGGAAAGCAAAGCGUGAGCCCCCAAAUCCACACCUGGGAGGAACGUUCCCCUUUGCAAGGCAUGGGACUGGCUGGCCCUGUGUCUCACGGGGGCUCUGAGUUUUGAGGUCACACUAGCCUCCUGAGGCCUGGCUGAGAGGGCUGGGUUGGGGGUCAGGAGGCCCCCUGUAGCCACGAAGCUCCUCUGGGGCAUUGUUAAAGGUUCACCCUCUUUUUUGUGGGUAUCCUGGAAGAUCUCAAGAAACUGAGCUUGGAAGAAGAGAGGCUGAGAGGGUCUCCCGCCGCCUGCGUUCUCUGCAGCUAUGGCCCCACAGCCUCCAGUGACCAUGGAGGGGAAGGUGCCACCCGCCUUGGCUGCUGAAAGGGUGAUGCUCUUAUGCCUGAGUCUUGGCUCCUGUGGUCCUGCAGAGACCCUGUGGGGGCCGCCCGGUCGUCACCUGCACUCAUCUUGGGUUUUCCUUCCUUUUCCACCCUAAGCUGAAGGUAUUUUUUUCCUGUUUUCUUCACUCUAACUUGGGGAAGAAGGAAGAUCCUUUAUGGAAAAGAAAAAAAAAAAAGCACCUUUGAACGUCCUGCAACUUGAGUUUCAAGCUUUCAGAAGGAUUCGGUGCUGCUGGCCUGCUCAGACCUCCGCCUGGGCUGUGGAGUUCCUCCUGUUGGCCCCUCCUCUCUGUACCACAAAAGCUCUAGGCGGCCCAGCCACCCCUGUGAAAGCGGCGCCCGUAGCCAGACGCCAAGGCUGCCGUCCCGAGCCGAGGGUGGCACCUUGCCCAGCGCACGUGCAUUCUCCUGUGGGAACUCGGAGGGCAUGUGGUGAGCAGUCUCCUGUCAGUUGAGGUGGAGGCUCCCGGCCCAUCUUUGCUCUCCUCAGGCUGCCCAGCUCCUGGCGGCACAUGGUGGCCUGGCAAAGCUGACUUGGCCUCCUCAGUUCCCCACCCAUCCGCGGAUCAUCGCCUUCCCUAGCCACCUCUCUCUAUAGCCACCGACAUCUGCGGAGCGUCACAGACUGGUUCUGAGCUGUGGUUUACAAAUUCAACCCAACACAGAGUGAAUUCAAAUUUGCUUUUGGAACAGCCUUUAUCUCCAAUUAAGUGCAAGUAUAUUUACACUAUGUGAUAUUAAAGGACUUCUCCAAUGACUGGGAGGUACUGAACCAAGAUGUUUGUAAAGAAACGGUGGGGUGAGGUGGUUAGGUAGAAUAUACCGUCCUGGCCAUUUCUCUUCCUUCAGGCGAGUAAGCGCUCCUUCAGCAGAAAGGCUGCGGAUUGCUGGCUGUGCUCUGUGGACUGGGCCAGUAGGUGUGGCCCAGGUCCAGGUCCUGGCACCUCUGCUGAGUGCCCAGCCUGAGAUGACACAUGCCAUCCUGGAGAGAAGCAGAGAGGGUGCUGUCUCCAGGCGUUCUCCAGACAGCCUGGGCCUGGCUUGCUGAGCCAGCUGCAGGAGGGGAUCUCCUGACUGGGGCUUGGGACCAGAUCUGCUGCAGAGAGGCAAUAACUCUGUCUAAAAAGAAAACUUGUCCCGUGUGAUUACAAAAACAGGAAAAGGCUCCAAGCUAGGAAAUGAGAUUUGAGGUAUGGAGAACAUUCUCACCUGAUGGAAGCAUCCUGUUCCUGUACAGGAGGAGGAGCUGGUGCAAGCCCUAGGCCACAUAUGUCACAGUUGUUUUGGACCCUCCGUAGCUUUUAUACUCAUAAAAUAUUAAAGUUGCCCCUUUCAUAUUUGGGUCAUUGAAAGAGCCCACCGUACUCUAGGUUCCUGCUCACUAUGCACAACAUCUCAGAAGAUGGCGUACAAAACUAUUUUUCUAACUAUAGCACAGGUAAUGUGGGGGUGGGGAGGCUUGGGAUAUACCUAAAUGUGGCAAAUGAUUUAUCUUCCACCUUGAGGGAUGAAAAGGAAACUAUGCACUUGAAUUUUAAUUAAAAUUUUAAUUUAAUUCAUUGGAUAGCUUGUGCCAGAAAGAACAGUCAAUAUUCAAGAAGCAAAACUGACGAUUAGCUCAGUUUCGGGCCUCCCUGUCGGGGGAGUUUUCUUGUCUGGAACACAAACACCUACAAGUAGAGUGUGAGCUGGUUCUUGACAAUCAGAUCUCAUCAACCCUUUGAAAUGUUCUGGGCAGCACAGCUCCUUGGUCUGCAUGGUUGGUGUAAGUAUAAUCAAGUAGUGAAAUUGUAUGGUAUAUACCUAUAUGCCAACAGUGUACACCCGUAUGUGCAGAAUUUGCUAAUAUAACCAUUUCAAUAAAAACCUAUUGAAAAAGCUGA